CUGGGGACCGCCAGGUGUUGUGGACCCCAAAGGGGUGACUACCUGCUCCUGGGCCCCACAGAGUCCUUGUGCUCAGUGUAGUGGCUGAGCUGGGGGAUGCCCUGGAACUCAGAGCACACAGCACUGGCUUACUGUGGUACCUGUGCAGUGAAAUUGAAGACAGAAUCACCAGGAUGGAACACAGGUCUUGCAGGAUCACGGAAAACCUUCUUAGAGUUGUCUUGACACCAGUGAUGUCGAGUGUCCGGGUGUUUGUAGGAUGGCUUGCCACUCAGUCCAGGGGCAGGAGCAACGGGGAGAUCCCACAAGCAAAGUGAACUGGGGGAUGGGCUGAAGGGGCUCCAGGCAACUGAGCCCUACUCGCAGGUCCUCGGCCUUGGCCCAAACAGGAAUGAGGGGCACAGAGUGCCCGGGUAACCGCUCCUGGGAGCAGUGGGGAACUGUCGGAUACUUGAACUCUCAAGAGCUGGGCUCUGAGCGUCCUCGUCCAGCUGCCAACUUGGCCAAAGGCUAAGCCAGCAGAUUGUUCUGUUGCCGGGCAACGCGACUUCUAAACCUGAGGGAGUGGGCAUGUGAGCACAUAAUGGCACCAGUGACAGAGCGACCAUAAUGGAUGAAUAAGCGCAGCCAGGUACCCGCGCAAGGCACCUGCUGGCAAUGGCAGGAGGCGGACGUGGGGGGUCGUGCAGUAGGGCUGGUGAAUUACCAGAUCUCCGUCAAGUGCAGUAACCAGUUCAAGUUGGAAGUGUGUCUUUUGAAUGCAGAAAACAAAGUCGUGGACAACCAGGCUGGGACCCAGGGCCAGCUGAAGGUGCUGGGUGCCAACCUCUGGUGGCCGUACCUGAUGCACGAACACCCCGCCUACCUGUACUCGUGGGAGGAUGGUGAUUGCUCACACCAAAGCCUUGGACCCCUCCCAGCCUGUGACCUUUGUGACCAACUCCACCUACGCAGCAGACAAGGGGGCUCUGUAUGUGGAUGUGAUCCGUGUGAACAGCUACUACUCUUGGUAUCGCAACUACGGGCACCUGGAGUUGAUUCAGCUGCAGCUGGCCGCCCAGUUUGAGAAUUGGU